CGAGAUGAAGUCUUGCUCUGUCACCCAGGCUAGAGUAUAGUGGCACAAUCUCGGCUCACUGCAACCUCUACCUCCCCAGUUCAAGCAAUUCUCCUUCCUCAGCCUCCAGAGUAGCUGGGAUUACAGGCGCCCACCACCACACCCGGCUGAUUUUUGUAUUUUUAUUAAAGAUGGGGUUUCACCAUGUUGGUCAGGCUGGUCUUGAACUCCUGACCUCGUGAUCUGCCCGUCUUGACAUCCCAAAGUGCUGGGAUUGUAGGAGUGAGCCACCCCACCCGGCCUGUUUUUAUUUGUUUUAAAUUCUUGUUUUUUCUAUAAAUUCUGAAGGUAAUAUUUUCUCAUAAAACAACAUCAAAAUCGUAGUAAAAUAGAAAAAGAGCCCCCUCCCCAUUCCACUCCAUGUAGUGUAACUUCUGUUGAUGUUUGGGUUUGUGUUUCUCUAAUCUCUAUGUGUAUAACACAGACAGUUUUAUUGUUUUAAAAUUUGAAUGGUUCAUAUCAUACUAGUAUUCUGAAAUUUAUUUUUCUUUAAUAUUUUUCAAAUACUUAUCUGUCAAUAUAUACAGAUUUUUUUUUAAAUGUGUCUACCCAAUGUAACCAGCCAGUGUCCCUCAGAAUAUUCGCUUGGAUUUUUCAAUUUCUAAGUAUUACAAACAAUGAUAUGAAUAUCUAUGUACAUUAUCUUUGCAUGGGUACUGCUGAAUAUUUAUUCUGAGAAGAGAAUUGUUGGCACCAGGGAGAUGUUUGAUAGAUAUUGCCAAGAGCCUUUCUAAACACCCACAGUAUAUUUCUUGUACCAUGCUUGCCAACACUAUAUAAUAAUGAUUUAUUUAGAAUGUUGUCAAUCUACUGUUGAAAAAUUGAUUCCUCAUUGUUGGGAAUUAUAUAAACCAGUCCCAGAACAUCUGACUUGGGGAGUUCGGGAAUUUUUCUUUAAAAAUAUAAUAAAAUGGGAAUGGAAUUAAAUACACUUGAAUAUACCAUCUUAUUCUGAGCUUGUAAAAGAAUCUACCGCAUUUGUUACUAACUAUCCAUUUACUGAAUGGCUGGAGAUACUGAUACAUGAUAAUGAGCAUUUCUAGAUUGCAAACAUGUGGACCAUGUUUGCAAUAACAACAUGUUGCAGUUGUGAUUUUGUGGUUUGUAACUACAUGUUUUCCUUCCAAAGAGAAGAUUCACACCCCUAGGGCAAAAGUAUGAUUUUAAAUGAGGUGUUAUAGCUCUGGGUCCUUUAAAAAGUUAUCCAUGCAAAUGAAACUGGGUAUGUUGUUGAAACAAACACAGUCUUGCAAUUACUUCUCUCCACCAUCCUCAAAGGUAUUUAUACCUAUUGGUGUCAGUCCUGACACUCAUAUAGAGACAUAAGGAACUCUGCAAAUAUGGCUUACUCUUAUUCUUAUGUUUUAAAGAAUACGCACGCACACACACAUAUAGAUCAGGUAAUUCUUAUUGAAUACUUAAUAUGCACUAGGUACUAUUGUAGGCAAUUUAUAUGCCUUUUGCUUUUUAGAUUCUUAUAACAAUCCUGUGCUGUUCAUAUUAACAUUCUUCCUACUUUACAGACGGAAAAAGUGAACCAGAGAGAAAUGAAAUAACUUGACUAAGGUUACACGUUUACAUGGGAUAGAGCUGGGGAUUCAAAUGAAGGCACGUCAGCUCUAGGUCGUGAACGUAACUAUGGCUGCUCCAUGUCCUCAUUGAGUUGCUUGCUGCACAAAGGUGCCUAACUGAGCAGAGGAACGGUUGAAACCUUUACACUACCCACAAACCAAACCAUGUCCCUUUGUUCUUGGCUGAAUAUUCCCUGGGGAAGGCACUUUUCUAGGCCACAGAAUAUCUGUAAGAGGUAUCAGCACCCUUGCUGCUGUUGGAUAAUUUGUAGGAGCUACACAGACCUAUUGGUUUCCAUAUGUAUCUUUGUAACUCAAUACUAUUUACCUACUCAUUAUGGGUAGAACUUAAAUAACAGAUUUGCCUUAUUGCCUGUUCUUCCCUACCUUAUAUUUUAAAACAUGUUGACAGAGUAUGCUCUUUACAUGAUAGAAUUAGCUGAUAACAUCUGAUGUUCCCCUGAAAACCUUUUAUUUUAUCAAGAUGGUUUCCUGGAAAACGAAUAGGGAGUUCACUUUUUUUCUUUUUGUGUGACACUCAACAUUUUGAAGAACAUGAAGGUCUUUAAGGAUGACUAGCUUCAUGGGAAGCUGCGUGGUGUAUAAGUCACAAGGGCAGGCCUCGUUGUCAGAUGGCAAGGUUUACAUCCCAGCCCAGUUAUUCACUAAAUGGGAAGGGAGGGGUGCUUGGGCAACCUAUCCUCUUUGAGGUCCAAUUUCCUCAUUUUUGAAAUGUUUGCAAUUAUAAUACCUAUGCCAUAUAAUUGGUAGGGUAAUUACAUAUGCUAAUCCAUGGGAAACAUUUAGAACAGUGCCUGGCACAUUGAGUACCAGGUAUGUGUUCUGUGUUGCUGUUCUUAUGGUAGAGUGAGAUAAUGCAUCUACAGCACUGCUUGACUUGUUGUAAGUUCUUAAUAGGUGUUACUUGUUUUUAUUGAUCUUCUCUCUAGAGAUUAUUAUAUUUAUAUACACAAAGUACUUAUAACUUCAGAAAAUUGUGGACCGCUGGAAACCUGUCCAAGCCCUCUAAUAGGCCUUGGAGAUGUAUUGAUGAAUAAGAAAGAGAGUCUCUAAUUUCUUGGAGCUUUCAGCUAAGCAGUGUAGAGAAAAAUCACACCAAGUAUAGUUCCAUGGCUGGAACAUUGGCUUUGGAGUUAUUCCUACCUGUGUGCAGAUCUCAAUUCUGCCGCCUGUCAGUUGUAUAUCCCAGAGCAAGUCAUUUAAUGUUUCUUCAGAUUAAAUAGCUAUGAAAUGAGAAAAUAGUUCUUACUUUCAAAGUACAUAUGGAUAAAUUCUUGCAUUAUUUAAAUUAAGCAUUUUGUCUGUUGAAUGUUUGACACUUCCUACACUCUAUUUCAGUAUAGAAGAAUCAUAUUUAUAAAGGAUAACAAAAAAAUUGACAAGAAAUCUAGGCAGCUUUUCCCCCAUCUCAUUUAAAAGUAUCAUUAUUUAAUAGUAGGAUAUCAUUUAAAAGUAUGAUAACACCUGGAUCUGACAAUUUAAUGUUUUAAGUAUUUUGAAUCUUUGUUCCCGUGGGCUUAUGCACUGUCUUGUGCUUUGCUUAUGCUCUUGGCUGACUGAAGAUUAUGGACUGUGUUUUAGAAUUUUUUUUUUUGCAUUUUCUUAUUUCAGACAUCAUAGUUACAGGUUCCAAAUAAAGUUAAUAUAUAUUAUUUUAGCAGGAAUUAAGUUAUAGGGUCUCUACACGGUACCUGGAAUACAAAUAUAAGUAUCACUGCAAACAGUGAUAAUCUACCUUGAAGACAAACAUAAGGUGACACUAUUAUAUUAGGAUAACAGAUAAUUAUAAUUAGUAUAAUACCGUGGAAAACAGAAGCAAAAAGGGUACAUUUAGCUUGAGUAGCCUGGAGAUAUUUCAGGGAAGUGUUAAUGACUUCUGAUGAGAACUUGCUGAGUAGAGAAGAAUUAGAAAAGUAUUUGGGGCAGAGGAGAUCAGACUUGCAGUAGGAAUAGUAGCAAGAGAUGAAGUGGGGAAGGAACACUGGGCCAGAUUCUAACAAUAUUGAAUGUGGGUAACAAGGAUUGGACAAUGUCUGCAAGGCACCGGGAAGCCAUCACAAUCUUUAAGCAGGUUGAGUUAAGAUUUUUUUUCUUAAGAUUGACUGGCAGCAUUUUGGAAAAUGGGUUAAAGACAGAAAGAAAGGGAGAGGAGAGGAGGACAGGAGAGGACAAGGGAGGGAAGGGGAGGGGAAGGGAGGGGAGGGGAGGGGUGGGGAGGGGAAUAGUGAGAACUACGAUAGUGGCCAGUGGCAAUGAAGGUGAGAAGACAUUAGAAUCUGUAGGUUUCAAAGGUAUUUAAACUGAAUUGAUCAAUUAUAGAAUAUGUAAGAUGAAGGAGUGAGAGAGAUUGAAACUGACCUACAUUUUUAUAUUUCUCAGCAAUGACUUAGAAACAACUCUUUCCUAAAGUUCUCCUGUCUGGCUGGGGAUACCUAUAAAAAAAAAUUAUUGGCUGGGUAUGGUGGCUCAUGCCUGUAAUCCUAGCACUUUGGGAGGCUGAGGCGGGUGGAUCACUUGAGGUCAGGAAUUUGAAACCAGCUUGGUCAACAUGAUGAAACCCCACAAAAAAAUGAGCAUGGGCAUGGUGGCGGGCGCCUGUAAGCUCAGCUACUUGGGAGGCUGAGGCAGGAGAAUUGCUUGAACCUAGGAGGCUGAGAUUGCAGUGAGCCGAGAUUCUAGCAUUACACUCCAGCCUGGACGACAAAGAGAGACUUUGUCUAAAAGAUUUAAAAAAAAAUAAAAAAAUUAUUAUUCACCAUGCUAAGUAUAAUUGUUGAGUCCUGGGGAAGUAUUAUUAAAACCUAGUGAAAAGCCAACUCACUUUUCCUGGAGUAGGUUAAGAAAUUAAAUAUAAAUUCUUUAUUUUUAAGUCAGGUUUAUUGAGAUAUAAUUUGCAAUCAGUAAAACCCCUUUUUAUGCAUGUGCUUCAGUGAGUUUUGACAAAUGUAUGUAGUUUUGUAACCAUUACCACAAUGAAGACAAAGAACAUUUCUGCACCCAUCCCCCUCAAACUCCCUGUGCCUUUUUGUAAUUUUUCCCUCCACUACACCCCAGGCAACCACCGAUCUGAUUUCCGUCAUUAAUGUUGCCUUUUCCAGGAUAAUAUAUAAAUGGAAUCAUAUACUAUGUACCCUUUUAUGUCUUUUUUUUUAAUUUAGCAUAAUUAUUUUGAGAUUCAUUCAUCUUACUUUGUGCAUCAGGAGUUUAUUCCUUUGGGGGAGAAAAAAAAACCUUGGAUUUAUGAGGUGUUAUUGACAUACCAUAAACAGCGUAUAUUUAAAGUGUACAAUUUGAGAAGUUUUGAUAUAUGUAUAUACCCAUGAAAUCACCACAGUAAAGAUAGUGAAUAUAGCCAACACCUCCAAAGGUUUUCUAAAGCUCUUUUAUACACUCUUUCUCCUGUUCCUUGCAUUCCCUUCCUUCCCUGUCCCAAAGCAACCAUUGAUCUACUUUCUGGACCUGUAAAUUCAUUUGCAUUUUCUAGAAUUUUAUAUCCAUGGGGUCACGCAGUAUUAUUUUGUGUCUGGCAUAUUUCACUCAGUGUAAUUAUUUUGAUAUGCAUUUAUUUGGUUGCAUGUAUCAAUAGUUGUUUUUAAAAAUAUUUUUUGCUAAAUAGCAUAAUGUUGUAUAGAUAUUCUGCAAUUUGUUUAUCCAUUCACUUGAUGAACAUUUGGCUUGUUUCCAGGUUUUGGCUAUCACAAAUAACGCUGCUAUGAACUUUCUUGUAUCAAGUCUUGGUGUGUACACUUACAUUUGUCUUAUAUGAUUACCUAGGAAUAGAAUGGUUGGAUCAUAGGCAAAGAAUUACCAAUCUGGUUUCCAGAGUAGUUGUCCCAUUUUACAUUCCCACCAGUAGGGCUUGAGAGUUUCAAUUUCUUUACAGCCUAACCAACACUUGGUAUGAUCAGUCUUCUAAUUUUAGACAUUCUAAAAGAUAUAAGAUAUUUCAUUGUGAUUUUAAUUUGUAUUUCCCUAAUGACUAAUGAUUCUGAACAUCUUUUCAUGAGCUUAUGUAACAUAAAUGAUUAUCUUUGGUGAAGUUUUGUUCAAAUCCUAUGCAGUCCCCUUCUUUUAAAAACUGAGUUGUUUGUUUUUUUUCAUUAUCAAGUUAGAAGAGUUCUAUAUAUAUUAUAGAUAUCAGUCCUUUUCAAGAUAUGGGUUUUGAAAAUAUUUCUCCCCACAUGAAUUUAUUCUUAUACAAGGGAUAGGAUUUGAUCAAGAGAAAAAGGGUAAAGAUAUUAUAUUCAUAAAUGGGAAUAGCAUGUACAAAAAAAGAAAUAAAAAAUUGGAUUUAUGAGGCCUCAAUAUGGAGUAAAAUAGAAAAAGGUGAUAGAAAAUGAGUUUUCAAAAAUAAAGAGUAGCCUGAAUAUAAAGACUUAUGGAAUUUAGACUCUUUUUGUGAGCACCAAUACUAAUAAAUAUCAAUACAACAACAAUAGUUAUACUAAGAAUUGAGCAUUGCAGUUUAUAGAGUGUUUUUAUAUACACGGUCUACAGUGUUUCCCCCUGGAUCAAUUUGCUUUAGUCCUGUGACAACUAUGUGAAGGCGCAGAGACUCGGGGCCAUGUGAAGUCAAUAUCAAAUAUAGGUUUUUGGGGUUUAAGCCAAUGCCUUUUCAACCAGUGUGUGCACGUGUGUGUGUUGGGGGGUGGGGGGCAUGUAUAUGUACAUUUAAUGGAGUGUGAGGAAAGAAUGACAGCUGGAUUGGUCUACAAAGGCUCAGAAGGGCACUUUCCCAAUAGGGCAGGGGAGAGUGUCCUGCUGAGCUCUGGCAGGUGGUACAAUAGGUUCUGAUAAAGUUUGGGUUGUAUACCCGUACUUUAAAAAUGACAAUUCACAGUUAUUAUAGAAUGGUUCACAAAAAUUUCAAAAUCUCAGAAGAUAUUUUAGAUUCUGUGAAUUUUUUUUAGUUGUCUUUUAUUUGUAACCUGACCCUAGAUAAAUAAAGUAAAAUGAUAUGUUAGUUAAUUUGUUAAGACAAAAAUAAUGUGAUCAAGUUCUUUUCUUUAUUUUUAAUUUUGUUGUUUUAUUUUUAAUGUCUCAUGGGAAUUCAAAGAACUUACUUUUUCAAACACAGUCCUUUUGUUCAGUAUAUUCUGAUUUCAUUGUCUUGCUCAGGGCUCUGCCCUGACUUUUUUCUGCAUACGGCUGACAUGCAAUUAGAACAUCAGAUCAACUUCGGAAACAUGAAUAAAAAUUACCUGCUGAAUAGACUCAUGAUUUGGACAUUUUCUUUUUUUUCUUCAGUUUUUGAACUUACUUGGAAGCUUUGAAAUGUCCUGAUUUGCUGUGUUUUCAAAAUUUUCACCCAUUUUUAACUCCUAUAGGUUCUUUUUAUGGUAAAGUACCAGUGGCUUAUAACCGAGAGAAACUGAAGUCUACUUGCCAGUGUGUGGCUUCUCCAUAUUAAAAUGCUGUACCCUUAAAAGGAAGGUUCAACUCUGGCUAUCCCUGAGAUGAAUUGAAUUAUCAGCCAGGAAAAAACUUUCGUUCCCUGGAAUUUUGAAAACAUGAUUGCUGCCUUGACCGUCCCUGCUCUUGAAGAGCACCAGCGAAAGCAGCCAGUCUGAGAUAUUGACACUACAGAAAAAACUGACAGCUUACUCCUUGUAUUGAUUCUACUCUUCUCUACAAAUAUAGACUCCGUUCCCUACCACAGCCUUAUAGUUCUGCCCCAGAGACAAGUAUGAAUACCACAGACAACGGUGUCAACUGUCUGUGUGCUAUCUGUGGGGACAGAGCAACAGGAAAACACUAUGGGGCAUCCAGCUGUGAUGGGUGCAAGGGUUUCUUCAGACGCAGCAUUCGUAAGAGUCACGUUUAUUCUUGCAGGUUCAGUCGGCAAUGUGUUGUUGACAAGGACAAAAGGAAUCAAUGUAGAUAUUGUCGAUUAAGAAAGUGUUUUAGAGCGGGAAUGAAAAAAGAAGCUGUACAAAAUGAACGUGACAGAAUAAGCACCAGAAGAAGCACAUUUGAUGGCAGCAACAUCCCCUCCAUUAACACACUGGCACAAGCUGAAGUUCGGUCUCGCCAGAUCUCAGUCUCAAGCCCUGGGUCAAGCACUGACAUAAACGUUAAGAAAAUUGCAAGUAUUGGUGAUGUCUGUGAAUCUAUGAAACAGCAGCUCUUAGUCUUGGUGGAAUGGGCUAAAUAUAUUCCUGCCUUCUGUGAAUUACCAUUGGAUGAUCAGGUGGCACUGUUGAGAGCUCACGCAGGGGAGCACUUACUGCUUGGAGCUACAAAGAGAUCCAUGAUGUAUAAAGAUAUUUUGCUUUUGGGAAACAACUAUGUUAUUCACCGCAACAGCUGUGAAGUUGAGAUUAGCCGUGUGGCCAAUCGUGUUCUAGAUGAGCUGGUUAGACCAUUUCAAGAAAUCCAGAUUGAUGACAAUGAGUAUGCUUGUUUAAAGGCAAUUGUAUUUUUUGAUCCAGAUGCAAAAGGGCUAAGCGAUCCAGUAAAAAUUAAGAACAUGAGGUUCCAAGUGCAGAUCGGUUUGGAGGACUACAUCAAUGAUCGGCAGUAUGACUCCCGGGGGAGGUUUGGAGAGUUGCUUCUGCUCCUGCCCACACUGCAGAGCAUCACGUGGCAAAUGAUUGAGCAAAUACAGUUUGUUAAACUUUUUGGGAUGGUUAAAAUUGACAAUCUACUUCAGGAAAUGCUAUUAGGUGGGGCUUCCAAUGAUGGCAGUCAUCUCCAUCAUCCAAUGCAUCCACAUUUGUCUCAAGACCCAUUAACUGGACAAACUAUACUUUUAGGUCCCAUGUCAACACUGGUUCAUGCAGACCAGAUCUCAACUCCUGAAACCCCACUCCCUUCCCCACCACAAGGCUCUGGGCAAGAACAGUACAAAAUAGCUGCAAACCAAGCAUCAGUCAUUUCACACCAGCAUCUCUCCAAACAAAAGCAAUUGUGAAAAUGUGUUUACUUCAGAACGGCACUACAUAAAUGUGAAAAGUUGUUGAUCUUGAAAUAUCUCAGGAUAGCACUUUUGGCAAACUCUUAGCCAAGGCUUCUUCAUUGGUGCUGUUAUAAGAUGGUGUCCUAUUUUCUUGUUUAUACGUUCAUUCUGUUUGUUAUUGCUACUAUGUAAAACUUUCACAUGCAACCAAUGUAUAUCUGAGUUUGAAGAUGUUUAUAUAGGGUAUUUUUUCCAACUGCCCCUGCAUUGUGCCUGAACCAAUUGAAUCUUAUGUAUGAGUUUCAUUUGUUUUAUUAAUGUUAAUUUAAAUCUGUAAAUAAUUGCUUUAUUGUGAUGUGAUACAGAACAAAGUGUUCGUUUUUGACUGAAAAUAGUAGAUCAGAAAUCUCAGUUUAAUAUAAAAUGAGCUAAGUUUUUAAAAAUAAAUUAUAAACUUGGAGAUUAGAAAAAUAAAGCAGUUGCUGUAGAAUAGGCUGUAUCUUUUUCAAGAAGAAUCUCUUAUGGACAGUCUGUGGUAAAGAAGCAACUCUUUGCUUUAGAGUUAAAUAUUCCUAUCUUAAGUUUAGAAAAAUACAAAAAACCAUUCCAAGGAUGACUGGAUACUUUUUGAAAUCUGACUUUCUUUGAAGAUGUAUGUUAAGCAAAAACAUGUUGCUUUUAUCAGUUAGGAUACAGGGUGAACUGUAACAAAGAAACCCCUAAAACAGUGACUAAAUCAAGAGAGGAAUCUAUUUCUUUCUCCUGAAACAAUUUAGAAAAUAGUUAUCCAUUGACUAGAAAUUAGUACAUGCCCACAGCUGGCUCCCACGGUAGCCAGGAGAAUUAUCUAUAGGUGGAAAGUCUGUGUCAGCCAAAGCCAUGUCACUCUGAGAGAACUGAUUCUGAGGACAAGUUAGCCAUCUACCACCCAUGUCCCUUAUUUGGUCCUCACAAUAACACUUUAGGAGAGAUAUCAUUAUCGCUGUUUUAUAAAUAAGGGAAACUUUAGCUUGAGGGUUUAAGGAACAUAACCAAAGUUCACAAACAUAACGAGUGAGAGAAACACAUUCAAGCCCAGGUCUAGUUGACUUUAAUGAAUCUUUGGUGUGGAAUGAAAAAUGUGAACUUCUUACUCAUAGUGUGGUUUUUAAAUAUAUGCAGUUGAGUGAUGAUUGGAUACUAUUCAUCAUAUUGCCUAUAAUAUAUAUUUACCGAUAAGCAGUGAGUGUAAAAUUGUUGUAGCUUGAAUAAGAAACCACUUUUGUAGUUUUAACCAGACUUUCUCUUAAAAACAUUAGAUAAAAUAAAAGAUUCACCGGAUGGAUUCUGAUGAAAACGAAAACAAAGUAAAAUGACUGGCUUAGCAGAUUCUUUGAAAUGUAGCAGCCCAGGGAUGUACCAAAUGUCGAAUUCUAGACUGAGGAGUAGAGUUCAUUGGAGUCUUAAACUCUCUGAUAUCACUUAAAGCUGGAGUUUAUUUUAAAACAAAUGAAGCAUGGGCCACCUCAUGAUGCAGUGGCUCCUCUCUGGUUGAGGAGAGGGAAAAUUGGAAAAACUGGUCGAGUAAUUAUCAAUAAUUUUUUUUAAAAAGAGGAUCCCAAACUGUAAAAGAUUGAAAUAAUCUUUCUCAGGAUUUUUUAAAUGUCUAAGAUUAUGAUGUCAUAUCUCCCACUUACCUUAUAAGUAAAAAGGUUAAUAUCAAGUAACUUAUUAGCUCUUAAAGUAAAAUUGAACUUAUUAAAAGCUAUCUAUGAUUUAAUAGAUUUAAUAAAAUUCCUUCACGACCUGGUACCCUUGUGAAACUGUAAAAUAUAUCAUAUGGGGGGAGUUUUUUAACUCUUAUUUUUUGAAAAUUUACUGUAGCUUCUAUUUCGUGAAUAAGAAUGUUUUGAUUUUGAUCAUACAAAUAACUUUUGUAGAUUUUUGUUUACUUUUGGGGGGGUUCCCUUAGAAGACAUUAAAAAAAAAUACUGCCUUGGUCUGUGCAGGCUGCUGUAAUGAAAUACUAUGAACUUGGCAGCUUAUAAACAACAGAAAUUUAUUUCUCGCUGUUCUCAAUGGUGGGAAGUCCAAGAUUAAGGGAUCAACAAAUUAGGCCUCUGGAUCAUACAUGGCAUUUUCUAGCUGUGUCCUUAUACAUAAAAGGAAAAAGGUAGCUCUCUCGAGUCUCUUUAAUAAAGAUACUAAUUCUCAUGACUGAAUCACCCUCCAAAGGCCCCACCUCCUAAUACCAUCACUCUGGGGACUAGGUGUCAGCAUGUGAAUUUUGGAAAACACAAAAAUUCAGAACAUAGCAAAUACCUUUGAAGUAUAAAAGAUAAAAUUCAUUUUUAGUGAACCCUGUAAUUUAUUCGUGUAUAUUUACUAAACAGCUGUAUCUUUGAAAUUGUUAGUAAUGAUUCUGCUUCAAUAACUAUGGUCAGGGAAUUUAUAAUAUUAUAUUUUUAUAUACUGAACUGCCAUAGAUGCUGGAAAAAAGGAACUGAUGUUUUCAGCAUAUUUUCAAAAUAUUGAUAAGGGAAGUUAUUACUUUUAUAUAGUAUUCAACUUUUUUCAGGUAAUAGAAGUGAAUAAUUUAUUGUGAAAUAAUUCAUUUUAUAAAUGUAUAAUUAUUUUUAUAAAUUUUAUUGUUGGAAAUCAAAAAUUAGUAGAUUUUUUACCAUGUUAAAUUAUAGUGAGAUUAAAGUAUUACUAAACUGUGAUGCUAUGUUUGUUUCACUAAACUUUCUAAAUAAAAACUGAGAAAAAAAAAA